GCUGCGUCCGCGCCUUCUCUUUUCCGGUCCUCUCCGCCGGCCGGGGCUCGGCUGAGCUCCAGAUUUCCCCACCCGCGGCCGCCGCCAGGGGACAGGAGCCGAGGCGCGGCAGGGCACCAGCGGCGGGAGGCAAGGUUGGGGAGGCGAGGGCGGUCCGCGUGCGGGGGCGGGAGGGGGCUGGGGGAUUCGAGGGACGCGGCAGCCCCGCCCCCGCCCCCUCCUCUUCUCCGCUCCAAGCCCGAGAAGCUGGGGAGCAUGGACCAGACCCCGCAGCGCUGGCACCAUGACGCUCGCCCGCUUCGUGCUAGCCCUGAUGUUAGGGGCGCUCCCCGAAGUGGUCGGCUUUGAUUCUGUCCUCAAUGAUUCCCUCCACCACAGCCACCGCCAUUCGCCCCCUGCGGGUCCGCACUACCCCUAUUACCUUCCCACCCAGCAGCGGCCCCCGAGGACGCGUCCGCCGCCGCCUCUCCCGCGCUUCCCGCGCCCCCCGCGGGCGCUCCCUGCCCAGCGCCCGCACGCCCUCCAGGCCGGGCACACGCCCCGGCCGCACCCCUGGGGCUGCCCCGCCGGCGAGCCAUGGGUCAGCGUGACGGACUUCGGCGCCCCGUGUCUGCGGUGGGCGGAGGUGCCACCCUUCCUGGAGCGGUCGCCCCCAGCGAGCUGGGCUCAGCUGCGAGGACAGCGCCACAACUUUUGUCGGAGCCCCGACGGCGCGGGCAGACCCUGGUGUUUCUACGGAGACGCCCGUGGCAAGGUGGACUGGGGCUACUGCGACUGCAGACACGGAUCAGUACGACUUCGUGGCGGCAAAAAUGAGUUUGAAGGCACAGUGGAAGUAUAUGCAAGUGGAGUUUGGGGCACUGUCUGUAGCAGCCACUGGGAUGAUUCUGAUGCAUCAGUCAUUUGUCACCAGCUGCAGCUGGGAGGAAAAGGAAUAGCAAAACAAACCCCGUUUUCUGGACUGGGCCUUAUUCCCAUUUAUUGGAGCAAUGUCCGUUGCCGAGGAGAUGAAGAAAAUAUACUGCUUUGUGAAAAAGACAUCUGGCAGGGUGGGGUGUGUCCUCAGAAGAUGGCAGCUGCUGUCACGUGUAGCUUUUCCCAUGGCCCAACGUUCCCCAUCAUUCGCCUUGCUGGAGGCAGCAGUGUGCAUGAAGGCCGGGUGGAGCUCUACCAUGCUGGCCAGUGGGGAACCGUUUGUGAUGACCAAUGGGAUGAUGCCGAUGCAGAAGUGAUCUGCAGGCAGCUGGGCCUCAGUGGCAUUGCCAAAGCAUGGCAUCAGGCAUAUUUUGGGGAAGGGUCUGGCCCAGUUAUGUUGGAUGAAGUACGCUGCACUGGGAAUGAGCUUUCAAUUGAGCAGUGUCCAAAGAGCUCCUGGGGAGAGCAUAACUGUGGCCAUAAAGAAGAUGCUGGAGUGUCCUGUACCCCUCUAACAGAUGGGGUCAUCAGACUUGCAGGUGGGAAAGGCAGCCAUGAGGGUCGCUUGGAGGUAUAUUACAGAGGCCAGUGGGGAACUGUCUGUGAUGAUGGCUGGACUGAGCUGAAUACAUACGUGGUUUGUCGACAAUUGGGAUUUAAAUAUGGUAAACAAGCAUCUGCCAACCAUUUUGAAGAAAGCACAGGGCCCAUAUGGUUGGAUGACGUCAGCUGCUCAGGAAAGGAAACCAGAUUUCUUCAGUGUUCCAGGCGACAGUGGGGAAGGCAUGACUGCAGCCACCGCGAAGAUGUUAGCAUUGCCUGCUACCCUGGCGGCGAGGGACACAGGCUCUCUCUGGGUUUUCCUGUCAGACUGAUGGAUGGAGAAAAUAAGAAAGAAGGACGAGUGGAGGUUUUUAUCAAUGGCCAGUGGGGAACAAUCUGUGAUGAUGGAUGGACUGAUAAGGAUGCAGCUGUGAUCUGUCGUCAGCUUGGCUACAAAGGCUUUCAAACUUUGGAGGAAUGCACUGCGGUAGGAUUUGGAGUGAGUGCAAGAUAUGCUUUUUGUGAAGUGAGAGAAGAGAAAUUUUGAAAGAGAAGUUUGAUCUUGAUAGCAGCAAGAUUAUUUUUAAGAAAUAAUAUAUGUGAAAUUUGAGGAUAUAAAAAUUGAUUCACUUACAGCCUGUGUAUCCCUUGGAAAGUUAUUAUCUACCAGGAGCACUUGACAUCCAGUUUAAAGACUAAUUAUCAGAAAGUGUUGUGUCAUUGAAAUUUUCAGCUAUGAAUUACUAGAUUCAGUAAACCAGUGAGAAGCCUUUCCCUUUUUUCUAUGGAUGGCAGAGUCCUUAAUUGUUUAAAGAAAGAGUAGUCAAAAGAAAAUGUAUUAGAUUUCACUAUAUCAAUGAGAAUUUAAUCAUGUGCUGUUAUUUGUUAAAAUGUUCUCUAAUUUCUACUUAUUGAUAUAUCUAAAAUGGUGCUUUUUUUUAGUUUGUGCAAGUUGAUCAGUUGCUAAGAAAUGAUCCUUUUGGUUUCUUUAAGUGAGUUAAAUUUUACUUUCUGUAUGUCUACUUCUACCUGCCAUCUACUUUUAUGUUAUUUAUCAUGCUUUAUUUUCUGUUUUUUGUGUAAUCAUCUGUUUUUUGAUUUUCAUGAUUAAUUCAAUUUUCAAUUUUCAUCUUUUCUCAGUGGUCUAGAAAUUCAACAUUCUUAUUGUUUUUCUGGAAGUUCUCUUUAAAUUUUUAGCAAACAUACUGAAACAUACUUUCUUAAUAAUUUCAAAAAUUAUUAUCUGUAACUUCCCCUUCCUGAAAAAGAUAAAGACAUUUAACAUAUUGUUGUUUACUUUCUACCUCCACCCAUUCUCACCUCUGAAACUUCUGGGAAUCAUCUGGAAUUUUUGUUUCCAAAUUCUAUUAAUUUUUUAUUGUCUUCAAAUUAUGCCGAUUUGAAUUUCAAAUUUCUUUACAUUAUACCUAUACAUUAUCAGCAAUUAUUUUUAUUUUUAAAGAAGGUUAAUAAACAACAAUCUCAACAAUCUUAUGCAAUUUUGCCUAAGAAAAAGGAGAGACAAUACAAGUAAACAUAGAGAACAGAAAAGAAAUUUAAGCACAGAUAUAUAGAAGGUUAAACAAAAACUCUAGUAGAUUAACAAUACAGCUGGGCACGGUGGCUCACGCCUGUAAUCCCAGCACUUUGGGAGGCCGCGGCGGGCAGAUCUCUCGAGGCCAGGAGUUCAAGACCAGCCUGGCCAACAUGGUGAAACCCCAUCUCUACUAAAAAUACAAAAAUUAGCCAGCUGUGGUGGCUUAUGCCUCUAAUCCCAGCCGCUCGGGAGGCUGAGGCAGGAGAAUCGCUUGAACCAAGAAGGGAGAGGUUGCGGUAAGCUGAGAUUGUGCCAUUGCACUCCAGCCUGGGCGACUUUUCACCAGUCCUUAAGAAACAGUUUCUGAAUUACAUGAAUUGUUGCAGAGCAAAGAAACUUAUGGAAAUCUUUCCAUUUAUUUUAUGAAGCUAAUUUAAUGUGAUUUCAAGACUAGGUAAGUAAACACACAAAAAAGAAAACUAUACCUCAAUCUAAUGAAUCUACAUACAAAGUUAUUUUGCUAACAAAAUAUUAGCAAAUUUAAUUCUACAAUGUAUUAAAAGAGCAAUAUACCACCAGUAAGUGGAGUCUGUUGUAGGAAUGUAAGAGUGAUUCAAACUGAGACAUUCAAUUAAUGUAAUUCAGUGUGUCACCCAUAAAUAUACAAUAAUUUUAAUAAAUGAUUAAACAAAUAUCUUAAUAAUGUUGAAAAGUUAUAUGAUAAAAUCAACAUUCCUUCUUAGGAAGCUGAGAACAAAAUUAAACUGCUUUAAUUUUAUAUCACAAAUAAGCAUCAAAUAGGAACAAAAGAGUGCCUGCCAUUACUGCAAUGAUAGCAUUGUCUGGAGGUUGCACUAAAGCCUUAAGAAUUGAGGUAUCAGUAUUGAAAAGGAAGGGUCAGAAUAUUUAUAUGAAUAAUAUGAUUGUUCACCUAGAAAACCCAAGAGAAUCAACUGGAAAGAGACUAGAACUAGUGUUUAUUAAUGUAACAAGAUAAAACAUAAAUACUUAAAAGGCAAUCGUCUGCCUGUGGGAUAAGUAGAAAAUAAAAAGAAAAACAGAUCUGUAGAAGUUACAAAAACUAACAACAAAACAAAAACUAGGAAUACACUUUGUAAGAAUUGAGACCUAUGUGAAAAACCUAAGUCUUUACUAAAGCUAGAAGACCUUAUCAAUGAAGAGAUGUACCGCAAUCCUGAAUGUGAAGACAAAAUAGAAAUAAAUUUAUACAUUAAAUACUAUGCUAGUAAAAAUCUUUCAUUUUUCUUGGUGUGCAUAUGGGGUGGGGAGGGGGAUUUGACUUCCAAAUUCAUCUGAAAUCCAGUCCAUGUGGUACUGGCACAGGAAUAGUCAAAGAGGUCAGUGACACUGCAGCAGUGGCUUUCAACCUUGGUUUUAGAUUGAAAUCAUUUUGGAACUUGAAAAAACACUACCCAUUCUACUUUAAUUCAUGUGAGAUGAGGUUCAGGUUGUGCUAUACUUUAAGUGUUUUCAAAGGCAAUUCUGAUGGGUAGCCAAGGUUGUGAAUUACUGAACUAUAAAGACCAAGAAAUGGCUUGUGCACAUAUAGCAUGAUAAAUAAGAAAGACUUUCAAAUCAGCAGGUUAUUGGGACAACUACUUUAAGGACAAAAAUAAAGCUAGAUUUCUUACUAACACUAAUAGUAAGACAGAAAUAAAUUUCAGACAGACAAGAACCGUGAUAUACAAUAAAUACAUAAAAUUUAAAAAAUGCAAUAAAUAAUAUAAUUAAUUAAUUGAUUAAAAAAUAGAAAAAAGUAGAAUAAAACUUCUAGGAAGAAAUCUAAGCUGCCCACAAAGAUUUAUGUAUAAGGAUAUAUAUAUAAUUGUAAGAAGUCUAAUAAUUUUAAAACACAUGCGCAACAAUGAAGAAAUAACUUAGUUUUCUUUGCCAAAGUUUGAUGGAGAACUAUCCGCAGAAGAAUCACCUACAGUUUUGUUAAAAACAGAUUACUUAUUUUUUAAAUGAUUUCUUUGUCUAUUGUAUGCCAUUAUUCUCUACUAGAAAGUAUAUUCACCAACAAAUAUAUUUCUAGAAAUAUCAACUUUUAAAUUUAUCUUUCCACUUUCCUUGGAGUAGUUUUUAGGAAAGCUACAUUCUUAAUUUUUAAGUUUAUCAAUUUUAAAAUUUAUAGUUUAUACCCUCUAUGUCCACUUUAUUAAGUUUUUCCCUAACUUGAGAUUUCAAGGAUAGUUUUCCAAUAAUUCAUCUGGAAAGCUUUUGCUUCUGAUAACUAUUUCAUUAAUUUGCUUGAAAGCUUUUGCCUUUGAUAACUAUUUCAUUAAUUUAUCAGAAAUUGAGUUCUAAAUAUGGCGUUAGUUUGAAAUAUUUAUUUCAUUUAAAUAUUUUUGUAUUUGCAUACUUUAAAAUGUGUUAUUAAACAAAAAAUUAAUAAACUAAAAGUAAAUCUGC